GCAGGCGCAGGCGCAGGCGAGGGGCUGGGUGGCGGUUGAGACAGCGGCGGUACUGGGAGGCGUAGGUGAGGGUCGCGAGGCUGCCCGAGCUUCUGAGCGAGCGCGGUGCUUUUGGGAACGCGGGACGGGCGAUCUGCGGCGCCAGGAGCUGGGCCGAGGCGCGGCGGCGCGGCUGCCGGCUGCCCUGUGAAUGGGAAGUUACGCGAAGUCCACCCAGCGUUUCUGAGGCAAUCUGAAGGCAAAUCCUGUUUAGACCCAGGCGAAGGUUCCCGGUGACCCGGGCUCUCACCAGCCAAUUGUCCCUUGCCGUCCUCCUGAGGGUGCCUGGAGCUUAAGCACUGUGUGCUCUUGGCCUCCACACUGGGGAUGCCGCUGACUCCCACUGUCCAGGGCUUCCAGUGGAUUCUCCGAGGCCCUGAUGUAGAAACUUCCCCAUUGGGUGCACCAAGAGCAGCCUCACAUGGUGUGGGCUGACAUCAAGAGCUGCCAGAUCCAACAGGUCCUGGGGGAGUAGGAGCCAGUGCAAGGAGAGAAGUCCAUUGAGAAAGGCAAAUGGAUGACAUCAGACCCAGGGGCUGAGGUCCCCAACUGCAGCUGGGUAGCUUCUGGAGUGGACAAGGAGCAACAGGGAAGUUCGUGGCCUGGUGUUCUGGGAUCCACUGUCUCAUCUCAUUCUUGUGGGCACCAGAACGUAUCCAAAGACAAGACUCAGUGUCUCUGGCAACAGUGAGCCAGAGAUAGAAUGUGUUUCAGAGGAGGAGGAAGGGGUUGUUGUACCCCAUGGAAACAGUAUAUUGUUUUACAGUAGCGUGUCUUUCUCUAAUAACUACUUAGCGUGUUCCUGUUAAUGGAAAAUAUUGGUGGUGUAAGUUUCCCCACUGUUCUCAUCUUCAUGUAAAUUUGUUCAUUUCCUUCCUUCCUUCCUUCCUUCCCUACUUCCCUCCAACUCUCUUUCUCUCUCUUUUUAUUCUUUCCCUCCUUCCCACCCGCCCUCCAUCCCUCCCUUCCUUCCUCCUUCCCUCCUUCCCUCCCUUCUUUCCUUUCUUCCUUUCUUCUUUUCUUCUUCUUUCUCUCUCAUGCUCUCUCUUUUUCUUUCCUUUUCAUUCUCUCUACUUUUUUGAAGAGAUCACACUGUACUGAAACCUACAUUAUUUUCCAAAAUCUCUGGAUCUGCUUCUGUCUUGCAGGCAGAGAGCUCAUCCAGUAGCCCUUAGCUCUUCCCAGCCCCCUCCUUUGAUUUGUGGGUGCCACUGCGGCAGCUGCUGAGUCUCAGUGGUUUCUGGUCUUCACCAAGUUCUGCCCACCCAGAUGGUUUUUACCUGUCCUCACCAGAAACCUGCACUGUCUAGAUUGCUGAGGCUGCUUCUCCUUAACCGAUCUGCUAUCUGUAUUCCAGGGGCACCCCAGGGUUAGAGGUAAAUGGCACAGGCCUUGAAAUCUCCAACUGCUCUGACUCCAGGAAGAUGGCCAAUCUUUCCUAAGCUGCUCACCUUACAAGAAAACGAAUCGUACUGCUAAGAAUUCAAACUUCAGCAGUCAUGGGGAGCCUUGGAAGGAGCCCGAAUCACUGAUGGAAUUGGACAGUGCAUGGAGAUGGUUCAGCAGGACAAGGUGCUGAAAACUCAUCCCCGUGUGACCUCAAAAUGUCAGGUCUCCCAGAUGCCAGAAAAUACAUUUACUUAAAGCCGUUGAUACGUCUUAAAGCGGUUUCCUUACAGUGUCAUUGGAGGACAGUGUGGAGUGCAGAGAGACAUGCUUUGAAAUGGGAUUGAUCCAGUCCUCCUUCCUUCACUACCACAUGAAUGCUGGGCAGCCCAGGGUCAACCCACCGCACCCUCAACUCAGACGGUUACCUGGCACGCUGGCCACAGUCUACCUCACUCUUAUCAGAGUCUGAGCUACUGGCAGUGCUUUCAGCUCUGAGUUCAGGCACCUCGAACCUUGUUUUUGUGGUGAAGGAUCCUAAAGUGCUGUGGGGAGUGAUCACAUUUUUCACAACAUCCCUGGCUCCACCUCUUCUGCCACAAACGUCAGCAUGGUGGUAUCAGCUGGCCCUUGGUCCAGCGAGAAGGCAGAGACGAACAUUUUAGAAAUCAACGAGAAAUUGCGCCCCCAGCUGGCAGAGAACAAACAGCAGUUCAGAAACCUCAAAGAGAAAUGUUUUGUAACUCAACUGGCCGGCUUCCUGGCCAACCGACAGAAGAAAUACAAGUAUGAAGAGUGUAAAGACCUCAUAAAAUUUAUGCUGAGGAAUGAGCGACAGUUCAAGGAGGAGAAGCUUGCAGAGCAGCUCAAGCAAGCUGAGGAGCUCAGGCAAUAUAAAGUCCUGGUUCACUCUCAGGAACGAGAGCUGACCCAGUUAAGGGAGAAGUUACGGGAAGGGAGAGAUGCCUCCCGCUCAUUGAAUCAGCAUCUCCAGGCCCUCCUCACUCCGGAUAAGCCAGACAAGUCCCAGGGGCAGGACCUCCAAGAACAGCUGGCUGAGGGGUGUAGACUGGCACAGCAACUUUUCCAGAAGCUCAGCCCAGAAAAUGACGAAGAUGAGGAUGAAGAUGUUCAAGUUGAGGAGGCUGAGAAAGUACUGGAAUCAUCUGCCCCCAGGGAGGUGCAGAAGGCUGAAGAAAGCAAAGUCCCUGAGGACUCACUGGAGGAAUGUGCCAUCACUUGUUCAAAUAGCCACAGCCCUUGUGACUCCAACCAGCCUCACAAGAACAUCAACAUCACCUUUGAGGAAGACAAAGUCAACUCAACUCUGGUUGUAGACAGAGAAUCCUCUCAUGAUGAAUGUCAGGAUGCUGUAAACAUUCUCCCAGUCCCUGGCCCCACCUCUUCUGCCACAAACGUCAGCAUGGUGGUAUCAGCCGGCCCUUUGUCCAGCGAGAAGGCAGAGAUGAACAUUCUAGAAAUCAACGAGAAAUUGCAUCCCCAGCUGGCAGAGAAGAAACAGCAGUUCAGAAACCUCAAAGAGAAAUGUUUUGUAACUCAACUGGCCUGCUUCCUGGCCAACCAGCAGAACAAAUACAAAUAUGAAGAGUGCAAAGACCUCAUAAAAUCUAUGCUGAGGAAUGAGCGACAGUUCAAGGAGGAGAAGCUUGCAGAGCAGCUCAAGCAAGCUGAGGAGCUCAGGCAAUAUAAAGUCCUGGUUCACUCUCAGGAACGAGAGCUGACCCAGUUAAGGGAGAAGUUACGGGAAGGGAGAGAUGCCUCCCGCUCAUUGAAUCAGCAUCUCCAGGCCCUCCUCACUCCGGAUAAGCCAGACAAGUCCCAGGGGCAGGACCUCCAAGAACAGCUGGCUGAGGGGUGUAGACUGGCACAGCAACUUUUCCAGAAGCUCAGCCCAGAAAAUGACGAAGAUGAGGAUGAAGAUGUUCAAGUUGAGGAGGCUGAGAAAGUACUGGAAUCAUCUGCCCCCAGGGAGGUGCAGAAGGCUGAAGAAAGCAAAGUCCCUGAGGACUCACUGGAGGAAUGUGCCAUCACUUGUUCAAAUAGCCACGGCCCUUGUGACUCCAACCAGCCUCACAAGAACAUCAACAUCACCUUUGAGGAAGACAAAGUCAACUCAGCUCUGGUUGUAGACAGAGAAUCCUCUCAUGAUGAAUGUCAGGAUGCUGUAAACAUUCUCCCAGUCCCUGGCCCCACCUCUUCUGCCACAAACGUCAGCAUGGUGGUAUCAGCCGGCCCUUUGUCCAGCGAGAAGGCAGAGAUGAACAUUCUAGAAAUCAACGAGAAAUUGCAUCCCCAGCUGGCAGAGAAGAAACAGCAGUUCAGAAACCUCAAAGAGAAAUGUUUUGUAACUCAACUGGCCUGCUUCCUGGCCAACCAGCAGAACAAAUACAAAAAUGAAGAGUGCAAAGACCUCAUAAAAUCUAUGCUGAGGAAUGAGCGACAGUUCAAGGAGGAGAAGCUUGCAGAGCAGCUCAAGCAAGCUGAGGAGCUCAGGCAAUAUAAAGUCCUGGUUCACUCUCAGGAACGAGAGCUGACCCAGUUAAGGGAGAAGUUACGGGAAGGGAGAGAUGCCUCCUGCUCAUUGAAUCAGCAUCUCCAGGCCCUCCUCACUCCGGAUGAGCCAGACAAGUCCCAGGGGCAGGACCUCCAAGAACAGCUGGCUGAGGGGUGUAGACUGGCACAGCACCUUGUCCAAAAGCUCAGCCCAGAAAAUGACAACGAUGACGAUGAAGAUGUUCAAGUUGAGGUGGCUGAGAAAGUGCAGAAAUCGUCUGCCCCCAGGGAGAUGCCGAAGGCUGAAGAAAAGGAAGUCCCUGAGGACUCACUGGAGGAAUGUGCCAUCACUUGUUCAAAUAGCCAUGGCCCUUAUGACUCCAACCAGCCACAUAGGAAAACCAAAAUCACAUUUGAGGAAGACAAAGUCGACUCAACUCUCAUUGGCUCAUCCUCUCAUGUUGAAUGGGAGGAUGCUGUACACAUUAUCCCAGAAAAUGAAAGUGAUGAUGAGGAAGAGGAAGAAAAAGGGCCAGUGUCUCCCAGGAAUCUGCAGGAGUCUGAAGAGGAGGAAGUCCCCCAGGAGUCCUGGGAUGAAGGUUAUUCGACUCUCUCAAUUCCUCCUGAAAUGUUGGCCUCGUACAAGUCUUACAGCGGCACAUUUCACUCAUUAGAGGAACAGCAAGUCUGCAUGGCUGUUGACAUAGGCGGACAUCGGUGGGAUCAAGUGAAAAAGGAGGACCAAGAGGCAACAGGUCCCAGGCUCAGCAGGGAGCUGCUGGAUGAGAAAGGGCCUGAAGUCUUGCAGGACUCACUGGAUAGAUGUUAUUCAACUCCUUCAGGUUAUCUUGAACUGACUGACUCAUGCCAGCCCUACAGAAGUGCCUUUUACAUAUUGGAGCAACAGCGUGUUGGCUGGGCUCUUGACAUGGAUGGUGAGUACAGGCUCAGCAGGGAGCUGCUGGAGGCAGUAGAGCCUGAAGUCUUGCAGGACUCACUGGAUAGAUGUUAUUCAACUCCUUCCAGUUGUCUUGAACAGCCUGACUCCUGCCUGCCCUAUGGAAGUUCCUUUUAUGCAUUGGAGGAAAAACAUGUUGGCUUUUCUCUUGACGUGGGAGAAAUUGAAAAGAAGGGGAAGGGGAAGAAAAGAAGGGGAAGAAGAUCAACGAAGAAAAGAAGGAGAAGGGGAAGAAAAGAAGGGGAAGAAGAUCAAAACCCACCAUGCCCCAGGCUCAGCGGCAUGCUGAUGGAAGUGGAAGAGCCUGAAGUCUUGCAGGACUCACUGGAUAGAUGUUAUUCGACUCCGUCAAUGUACUUUGAACUACCUGACUCAUUCCAGCACUACAGAAGUGUGUUUUACUCAUUUGAGGAACAGCACAUCAGCUUCGCCCUUGACGUGGACAAUAGGUUUCUUACUUUGAUGGGAACAAGUCUCCACCUGGUCUUCCAGAUGGGAGUCAUAUUCCCACAGUAAGCAGCCCUUACUAAGCCGAGAGAUGUCAUUCCUGCAGGCAGGACCUAUAGGCACGUGAAGAUUUGAAUGAAACUAUAGUUCCAUUUGGAAGCCCAGACAUAGGAUGGGUCAGUGGGCAUGGCUCUAUUCCUAUUCUCAGACCAUGCCAGUGGCACCCUGUGCUCAGUCUGAAGACAAUGGACCCAAGUUAGGUGUGACACGUUCACAUAACUGUGCAGCACAUGCCGGGAGUGAUCAGUCAGACAUUUUAAUUUGAACCACUUAUCUCUGGGUAGCUACAAAGUUCCUCAGGGAUUUCAUUUUGCAGUCAUGUCUCUGAGCUUCUAUACCUGCUCAAGGUCAGUGUCAUCUUUGUGUUUAGCUCAUCCAAAGGUGUUACCCUGGUUUCAAUGAACCUAACCUCAUUCUUUGUAUCUUCAGUGUUGAAUUGUUUUAGCUGAUCCAUCUUUAACACAGGAGGGAUCCUUGGCUGAGGAUUGUAUUUCAGAACCACCAACUGCUCUUGACAAUUGUUAACCCGCUAGGCUCCUUUGGUUAGAGAAGCCACAGUCCUUCAGCCUCCAAUUGGUGUCAGUACUUAGGAAGACCACAGCUAGAUGGACAAACAGCAUUGGGAGGCCUUAGCCCUGCUCCUCUCGAUUCCAUCCUGUAGAGAACAGGAGUCAGGAGCCGCUGGCAGGAGACAGCAUGUCACCCAGGACUCUGCCGGUGCAGAAUAUGAACAACGCCAUGUUCUUGCAGAAAACGCUUAGCCUGAGUUUCAUAGGAGGUAAUUACCAGACAACUGCAGAAUGUAGAACACUGAGCAGGACAACUGACCUGUCUCCUUCACAUAGUCCAUAUCACCACAAAUCACACAACAAAAAGGAGAAGAGAUAUUUUGGGUUCAAAAAAAGUAAAAAGAUAAUAUAGCUGCAUUUCUUUAGUUAUUUUGAACCCCAAAUAUUUCCUCAUCUUUUUGUUGUUGUCAUUGAUGGUGGUGACAUGGACUUGUUUAUAGAGGACAGGUCAGCUCUCUGGCUCAAUGAUCUACAUUCUGAAGUUGUCUGAAAAUGUCUUCAUGAUUAAAUUCAGCCUAAACGUUUUGCCGGGAACACUGCAGAGACAAUGCUGUGAGUUUCCAACCUUAGCCCAUCUGCGGGCAGAGAAGGUCUAGUUUGUCCAUCAGCAUUAUCAUGAUAUCAGGACUGGUUACUUGGUUAAGGAGGGGUCUAGGAGAUCUGUCCCUUUUAGAGACACCUUACUUAUAAUGAAGUAUUUGGGAGGGUGGUUUUCAAAAUUAGAAAUGUCCUGUAUUCCAAUGAUCAUCCUGUAAACAUUUUAUCAUUUAUUAAUCAUCCCUGCCUGUGUCUAUUAUUAUAUUCAUAUCUCUACGCUGGAAACUUUCUGCCUCAAUGUUUACUGUGCCUUUGUUUUUGCUAGUGUGUGUUGUUGAAAAAAAAAACAUUCUCUGCCUGAGUUUUAAUUUUUGUCCAAAGUUAUUUUAAUCUAUACAAUUAAAAGCUUUUGCCUAUCACUCU